ACAGAGUCCGGCAUUGGUCCCAGGCAGCAGUUAGCCCGCCGCCCGCCUGUGUGUCCCCAGAGCCAUGGAGAGAGCCAGUCUGAUCCAGAAGGCCAAGCUGGCAGAGCAGGCCGAACGCUAUGAGGACAUGGCAGCCUUCAUGAAAGGCGCCGUGGAGAAGGGCGAGGAGCUCUCCUGCGAAGAGCGAAACCUGCUCUCAGUAGCCUAUAAGAACGUGGUGGGCGGCCAGAGGGCUGCCUGGAGGGUGCUGUCCAGUAUUGAGCAGAAAAGCAACGAGGAGGGCUCGGAGGAGAAGGGGCCCGAGGUGCGUGAGUACCGGGAGAAGGUGGAGACUGAGCUCCAGGGCGUGUGCGACACCGUGCUGGGCCUGCUGGACAGCCACCUCAUCAAGGAGGCCGGGGACGCCGAGAGCCGGGUCUUCUACCUGAAGAUGAAGGGUGACUACUACCGCUACCUGGCCGAGGUGGCCACCGGUGACGACAAGAAGCGCAUCAUUGACUCAGCCCGGUCAGCCUACCAGGAGGCCAUGGACAUCAGCAAGAAGGAGAUGCCGCCCACCAACCCCAUCCGCCUGGGCCUGGCCCUGAACUUUUCCGUCUUCCACUACGAGAUCGCCAACAGCCCCGAGGAGGCCAUCUCUCUGGCCAAGACCACUUUCGACGAGGCCAUGGCUGAUCUGCACACCCUCAGCGAGGACUCCUACAAAGACAGCACCCUCAUCAUGCAGCUGCUGCGAGACAACCUGACACUGUGGACGGCCGACAACGCCGGGGAAGAGGGGGGCGAGGCUCCCCAGGAGCCCCAGAGCUGAGUGUUGCCCGCCACCGCCCCGCCCUGCCCCCUCCAGUCCCCCACCCUGCCGAGAGGACUAGUAUGGGGUGGGAGGCCCCACCCUUCUCCCCUAGGCGCUGUUCUUGCUCCAAAGGGCUCCGUGGAGAGGGACUGGCAGAGCUGAGGCCACCUGGGGCUGGGGAUCCCACUCUUCUUGCAGCUGUUGAGCGCACCUAACCACUGGUCAUGCCCCCACCCCUGCUCUCCGCACCCGCUUCCUCCCGACCCCAGGACCAGGCUACUUCUCCCCUCCUCUUGCCUCCCUCCUGCCCCUGCUGCCUCUGAUCGUAGGAAUUGAGGAGUGUCCCGCCUUGUGGCUGAGAACUGGACAGUGGCAGGGGCUGGAGAUGGGUGUGUGUGUGUGUGUGUGUGUGUGUGUGUGUGUGCGCGCGCGCCAGUGCAAGACCGAGAUUGAGGGAAAGCAUGUCUGCUGGGUGUGACCAUGUUUCCUCUCAAUAAAGUUCCCCUGUGACACUC